CUCCCGGCGCGGCAGCUGUCUGGGCUGCUGCGCGCCGCCUAGGUGUCUGGGCGAUCUAUGGGCAAGAGCAAGGGCCACGAUGACAGAUUACGGCGAGGAGCAGCGCAACGAGCUGGAGGCCCUGGAGUCCAUCUACCCUGACUCCUUCACAGGCAGAUGUCUCUCAGCUAUCCCUGUAUAGCUCCAGUCCUGUUCAUGUUCUCUCUCACCAGCAGUACAUCUGUGCUGUGAGGAUGUUAAGGGGAUGAGUGAAGAGGGGUUUGAGAGUGUCAUUAACUGGCUUGAUUGCACAUUGAUCCAACCCUCCUAACAACUAGUCUUCCAAAAUAUAAAUGGACUCUCCUGAUACCACAUUCUCCUUCAGUAGUGCUUCACUUGACAAGGUCCUGCUAAGUAUUAUCAGAAAAUCCACCCAGCUUCACCAUUACUGUGACGUCUGAGGCUGGAGAAAAUGAUGAAACUGUCCAGACUACCCUCAAGUUUACAUACAGUGAAAAAUACCCAGAUGAAGCUCCCCUUUAUGAAAUAUUCUCCCAGGAAAAUCUAGAAGAUAAUGAUGUCUCAGACAUUUUAAAAUUACUAGCAUUACAGGCUGAAGAAAAUCUUGGUAUGGUGAUGAUUUUUACUCUAGUGACAGCUGUGCAAGAAAAAUUAAAUGAAAUAGUAGAUCAGAUAAAAACUAGAAGAGAAGAAGAAAAGAAACAAAAAGAAAAAGAAGCAGAAGAAGCUGAAAAGCAAUUAUUCCAUGGUACUCCAGUUACAAUUGAGAAUUUCUUAAAUUGGAAAGCCAAGUUUGAUGCAGAACUCUUGGAAAUUAAAAAGAAAAGGAUGAAAGAAGAAGAACAAGCAGGAAAAAAUAAAUUAAGUGGGAAACAACUAUUUGAAACAGAUCAUAAUCUUGACACAUCUGAUAUCCAGUUCUUGGAGGAUGCUGGAAACAACGUGGAGGUAGAUGAGUCUUUGUUCCAAGAAAUGGAUGACUUGGAGCUGGAGGAUGAUGAAGAUGAUCCAGACUAUAAUCCUGCUGACCCAGAGAGUGACUCAGCUGACUAAUGGACUGUCCCCAUCUGCAGAGAGGCUUGACUGCCACAGCAUCUGUGGCUAUGCUCAGAGGGUUAUGAUUUUCCUUUCUUUUUUUCUAAGAAAAAAUUAUUUUCAGGAGAAUAUUCUUCUGAUAGCUUUCAUCAUUGAACUUAAUAAACUGACCUUAAAAUUUCAAAUAUAAAAUGUUCAAGGCUUCUUACUGUUGAGCACAAGGUUACGUAUUUAAAAUCACCUAGUAUUUGAGAGAGAUCCUGCCUAUAGCACCAAGACUCGAAGGUAGGCUGCUGCUGUGCACAUGAGUUUAUACACAGGAAAUUGGAAUAACUUGGAAUUUCUAUGCUGGAGACUUUGGCUACUUCUGGAUUUCAAGCAUUGUAUGAAGUGUGAGAAAACUGAGGUGACUAGCACAUUAAACCAUCCAGAUUCUAGCCUCCAGGCACACUAAAUUUAAGUCUUGAUAAAACCAGGAGGCCAUAUUAUGAUCAUAAGUAAGAUGAAGUUUAGCCUUCCUUUUAGUCCAUUUUGUAUUGCCGUAAAGGAAUAUCUGAGGCUGGGUAAUUUAUAAAAGGUUUGCCGGGUGCGGUGGCUCACGCCUGUAAUCCCAGCACUUUGGGAGGCUGAGGCAGGUGGAUCACGAGGUCAGGAGAUUGAGACCAUCCUGGCUAACACGGUGAAACCCCGUCUCUAUUAAAAAUACAAAAAAUUAGCCAGGUGUGGUGGCGAGCACCUGUAGUCCCAACUACUCGGGAGGCUGAGGCAGGACAAUGGCGUGAACCCGGGAGGUGGAGCUUGCAGUGAGCCGAGAUCACGCCACUGCACUCCAGCCUGGGCAACAGAGCAAGACUCCGUCUCAAAAAAAAAAAAAAGGUUUAUUUGGCUCAUAAUUCUGGAUGACCAGAAAGUUGAAGAUUGGGUAUCUGCAUCUGGUGAGAGCCUCACGCUGCUUCCACUCAUGGUAGAAGGGGAAGAGGCACUAUGUGUGUAGAGAUCACAUGGCCAGAGAGUGAGGGUGGAAGUGCCAGGCUUUUUUUUUUUUUUUAAACUAGCUUUGGUGGGAACUCCCUCACCCCUGCUCCCCACAGGAAGGCAUUAAUCUAUUUAUGAGGGAUCUACCUGCUAUAACCCAAACACCCCACCAGCCCCCAUCUCCCAACACCACCACACUGGGGAUUAAAUUUCAAUGUGGGAUUUGGAGAGGACAAAUAUCCAAACCAUAGCAGUCUUAAAGUAUUUAAAUUAGAAUUUAAAUUAAAAUUUAAAUUACAGUAUUUAAAUUAGAAUCAUUUGUGGAGUUUCUAAAAGGUAUGCAUUCCUAGGCCCCUCUCAAGUUAGAUUUAUGAACACUGAUCCCCAGUCUGAAUUUUAAAACAGCAAAAUCUCAUACUGGUUCUACAGAUUAUUCUGAUGCACAAUCUGGGUUAAGAACCACUGUCCUGUAGUCGUGAAGUCUAUAUAUUUUGGUAUUUUCUUUACCUCUUCUCUAAUUAACCAGUCUGAAGGAGUUUGAAUUUUGGGGAUCGUACAUUGUCUGCAAGAGAAACACAUUAACAUCCGUGCACAUAGAGUCCUUUGUAAUAAUUUGGGAUGAUUGACUUGGUGGCUCCAGGUAGGAGAGCCAGUCUUCAUGCAAGUUAUUCAGUCACUACAGUUUUGGAGGACUGACUCUUAACCCCAAUAGGAAAUCAGUUGUGCUAUUUUAAAUUCAUAAAGCUAUUAUAAAGAGCUGCCUCCAGUAAAAAAUACAUAUGCCACAUACCCACAAACAGCAAUAUUAAGCCUUCAUUUAUUGUUGGAGUUAGACCUUAUAAUCAAAAAGCAAAUUAUUUAAGAUAAAAUUACCAUUGAGGAGUUUAAUACUUUUCAAGGAAUCUUCACGUCAGCCUUGAUCCCAGACCAAUAGAAUGGAAUAACAACAGGAAUGUUCAGCAUUUCUUUGCAGAGAGAAAUCCAAAAGUUUGUCCUAUGUGAGAUUUUGCUUUUCCCAUCUUUUUGAAGCUGAUCAGCAGAUACAUAAGAACCUGGAAGAAGCUGCUCAAUUAAGGUUAAAAAAAAUAAAAAGCAAUUGUUAGCAAUGUGGUGCUGAAAUCAAGACUUAACUUUGAAGUGUCAAGAAUGAUAACCUCCCAUCCACUUCAUGUGAUUUUUAAGAAUAAAUUUUAUAUAUUUCUCCAGGUAUUAAAGUGGAUGUCCACCUUUGCCAUUUCAGAACCUAAAGGCAGAAUCUAAUGGUAAAAUGAAGACAACCUAGUUGUCUUCUAAUAACCUAGUUAGUUCUAAUAACAUUCUCAAAUAUUUUCAUCUAGAGUAAAUAUUUACUGUUGGCUUUGUAUUCUGGGAAUUAGCCCAAGACUAUGCUGCUCAAAUGGGUGCAAAUAUACUCUCAGGUUGCAAUAGCAUGACGAGUGGUAUUUGAAGCAAUAAUUGUUCCAUCUUGGAUUAUCGGUUUUGCUCUUUGAUUUGGUAAAGUUUUUGUUUUUCUACUCGUGCCAGUUGUAUUAAAAUGUCACUAGGUUAAAAACAAACACAGAUAUGUUUAUUCAUUACUGUAUCCCUGUAAUAAUGCCUGGCAUGCAGUAGGUCCCUAAUAUUUGUUGAAUGAAUGAAUUAUAGAAUAGAGUGCAAAAUUAAUUCUAAUGUAUUUUAAAGUAAAGCAUGAGAGUUCAAAGAAAUGUUGUAUUUGCCAUCUACAACUUGGAAUAAUGUUCCUUGAUCCUGCUUUACUUCAUGCACUUUUGCCAGCAGAGGUGGAUGCCUUAGGGAAAAAGUUGGAUAAAUGCUGAUCUAAGGCAACACGUCUAAAUGGUUAUGUGAACAUUUCCCAGUUGGGGUAAAACUAAGAGGAGUGAUAAUAACAUCUCAUCAAUUUAAAGGACAAGUUCACUGAUCGUACUGUCAUACUCCAGAGAUACAUGUGCCAAGAAGCAAAGAGAUGCACUCUUGUAUUCCAGAAAGAAGAUGAUUUGUAAGUGUUCAGUAUUUGUGUGGCAGCCCUUUUAGGUGUAAUGAAGUGUAACAGAAAAGUAAGUGAACUACUUCACAUAGCUCUUAAUGUUUGUCUUUCAGAGGACAUACGAGUCAGGCAGCAAAAGUUGGAGCCAUUGUAUGAUUGUGUGUCAAAAUGAGAGUCACACACUUCAAGAACUGUAGGAACUAAUUUUAGAAAAAGACUCUUCAGAACAGAUGACACAUGAAAUGUGAGUUUAUGUAAACAUGUAAAUUUGAGUAGCAUUAGUUUGUUUUCUGUUUAGGAACUGUAUCAGGGUGACAAAGAUGAAAGAAUGCUGCCAGAAAAGUAUAUUGUUAAAUUUUCAGGCCUCCAUUGGUGAAGUUUCAAGUAACCUUUCACUUAAGUUACUUGUGUCAGAGGAUGGAUGAUGGGGUCAUUUAAAUUGUUGGACAAAGCCAUGAAAGGACUUUUAAAAUUUUGUCAUAAAAAUAGCCAAUGAUGUUUUUAAUUUUACAUCUAAAACUAAUUUGCAUUAUCCUGUGUUAGUGACUGAAUCUCAACUCAGUCCUCAUUUUUUAGUUCAACUUUUGACAACCUUAUAUUCAUUGACACCAUGGACAGCACAGUAAAAAAAUACACAAAUUUCUUUUGCAGUUAUUGAUUUGGAAUGAUCACUUUAAAAGAGCCAUCAAAUACGCCUACAUAUUGAGCCACUCUUUAUCAUUAAGGUGAAAAGUUCAUUCAAUUAAGGUAUUUGAGUGCUACUAUGCGCCAGCCUUUCUUUGUGAUAAUGUUAAUUUUUUUUUUCCUCCCCUCCAUGAAGGGAAGAAAAAAAAAUUAAUUCGGCCAUGAAUUUUAAUAUUCUGGCCAGCACCUUAUCCAUUUGUAGCCACGCCAACAAAUUUAUUCUGUGAUAUACCAAACUUACAAAGUCACUCUGCGAUUUCAGUAAGGCCCAUUCCCAACAUGAGUGCUGCUGUCCACGGUACUGAACCAUCAAUGCUAAAUGGUAUUUAGUUGUGGAUCUUCAUCCUGUCAUGCAGCUAAAUAUUCCAGGAAUACUGAACCAAGUGAGGAGAAAGAUAGCAGUGGGUUGCUGCAAAGGAGGUGAGGGGAGGGGAGAGAUAGCAAGUGAGAAAAAGAGAGACUAGUGGUGAUGUUUUUAAGUAAUUGAAGUAAAAAAGAGAGAGAAAGAGAGAGAGAAGAGGUUCUACUCAGUCCACCAAAGCUUUUUAAUUUCCUUACAUAAUUAACAUGAUGAAUUUUUAAAUAAUUGUUAUAUUUAGUUUUGUUCUUCCACCUUUUGGCUAUUUCUACUACAUAUUUACUUAUCAUAAAAAAUACUUCCUAGACCUUCCUCUUAUAGCUAUUGCCUAUCUCUGCCUUUGCAGCUGUUCUCCUUUAAAGAGUAGUCUCCAUUAGUUUUCUUGACUUCUUCAUCUCCCUGCAUAAAGAUGAAGGGUAUUUAGCUCUGAAAAUCCUUUACUGUUGAAUAUUUAGAUUGUUUUCAAUUUUUACAUAAUGAACAAUGCAUCAUGGGAUUAUUGGCUGCAAAUAAAUUGGAAACAUAAAAGGUGUUUUAAGUUUAAAUUUUUUUAAAAAAACAGGUAAAAAUAAAAUAUUUGCCAAAGACUAA